UACCUGCUGCGGCCGCUUUCGGCAUGGAGGAAAUUUAUGCGAAGUUUGUGUCCCAGAAAAUCAGCAAAACCCGCUGGCGACCGCUGCCUCCGGGAAGUUUACAGACCGCGGAGACGUUCGCUACAGGAUCUUGGGACAAUGAGGAAAAUUAUAUUUCACUGUGGUCUAUUGGAGAUUUUGGAAACUUGGACUCUGAUGGAGGGUUUGAAGGAGACCAUCAGUUAUUGUGUGAUAUCAGACACCAUGGUGAUGUAAUGGAUUUACAGUUUUUUGACCAGGAAAGAAUUGUCGCUGCUUCAUCAACAGGAUGUGUAACAGUUUUCCUUCACCAUCCAAAUAACCAGACUCUGUCAGUCAACCAGCAGUGGACUACAGCUCACUACCACACAGGCCCUGGCAGUCCUUCCUAUAGCAGUGCACCAUGUACAGGUGUUGUGUGCAACAACCCAGAAAUCGUUACAGUUGGAGAGGAUGGUCGAAUAAAUCUCUUCAGAGCUGAUCACAAGGAAGCUGUAAGAACCAUAGACAAUGCAGAUAGUAGUACACUCCAUGCUGUAACCUUUCUUCGAACUCCUGAGAUUCUUACUGUAAAUUCAAUUGGACAGUUGAAAAUAUGGGAUUUCAGACAACAAGGAAAUGAGCCUUCUCAGAUAUUGUCACUGACUGGUGACCGAGUGCCACUCCACUGUGUUGAUAGACAUCCCAACCAACAGCAUGUUGUAGCUACUGGUGGCCAAGAUGGAAUGUUGAGUAUUUGGGAUGUUAGACAAGGUACUAUGCCUGUAUCUCUGCUGAAGGCUCAUGAAGCUGAAAUGUGGGAAGUUCACUUUCACCCAUCCAACCCAGAACAUCUUUUUACCUGCUCUGAAGAUGGAUCCCUCUGGCACUGGGAUGCUUCCACAGAUGUACCUGAAAAGUCGUCACUCUUUCACCAAGAAAAAUUCUGGAGCGGAGAGCAUGUGUGGAGCAUGCAUGCAUGUCCAUGCUAUAACUUCAUCUACAGAGAAACAAACAGUUUCAUCUAAGGAUUAACUAAGUAUGUACUUCGUUUUUACUUCCUUCCUCCCCUAACCGCACAGUCUUGAACUUGCAAGUUUACUUUUAAGGAACCUUGGUUAGACUGGAAAUAAAACUUUAUUCUGUGUCUACUAUUGCAAGGCACAGUAUUAGACACUGUGAAAAAGUAAAACAUAUAAAAUAUGCAUCCUGCUCUUAAGACAUAUUUAGUCAUGGACAGAGGCAUGGAUAGUUCAAUUAGGAUAUAAGAAUUGUUAUAAAGUAGUAAAUUAAUGGUACAUACAAGUGCUGAGGGUUCAAGGAAAGAGAAAAACAUGAAGUAGAGGUUGUCUUCAAAGUUUUCUUAGAGAAGGAAGUUCAGCCAUAUUUUAAAGGAUCAGCAAGAUUUUAAAUGUACUAAUCUUUAAGCUUCAAGACAUAGGGACUUGGCACAGAGCACUUAGCACAGAGCCUGGCACAUAGUAGGUACUCAGUCAUUUGUUGAGUGAAUUAAAUUUGUACUUAUUUGAUAUGACAGCAAGUUGAGAGGAAAGUAAGUUGCGAAUAAUGACUAAAAUUGAAAUAUACUGCCUCUGCCUCACUUUAUUCUAUAGUAAGUACAGUGCGCUGUUAGAGAUAAAACCUUAUAAUCUAGUAGUGUUCUAAUCUGCUUGUAAGAACAUUUAUCUAAAAAGCAUAAGAAUGAAAGAUUUGAGGUAAGGCGAUUAUAUUUUAAGAAAUAUAGUAACAAAUAUAUAUUUAGAAAUAUAUUUCUAGAAAUGUUCAUCUAGAAAUAUGUCUAGAAAUUCUUUCUCAUGAUCAUUUUAUUUUGUUAUUACCCAAGAGUUUAUAUUUCCAUGUAUUACCUACAUUUUUGGUUUCUUUUUUUUCUUUCCUUAUUCAACUUGUAUGCUGGCCGUUUUGCUACCUUUCUGAGACUUUCCAUUAAAAGAUGAACAGAAAGUCAGUUGAAAUCACCUGCUUUUCCUGAAGACUUCGAGUUUGGUAUCCAUAUUAUCCCAUGGAAAUUUGAAUAUUUAAUAUCACUGAAUAAGCCUUUGGUCCAAAGUGGUGAUGUAUAAUAAUGGAAUUAUUAGCCUAUUAUUCUGAGAAUUAAACACAUUGAUAUCAUCACCUUUCUAAAUAUCAGUAGAAGUUUGAAUGUUUACUAAUAUAAAAAUCAUCUUGAAAGAUUUCUUCCUUUUCUUUUUUUCUCCCAGGAGGAAGAAGCAGUACUUUUUUGUCUCAUAGCAUUAGUAACCAAGCUAAUGUUCACCAGUCUGUCAUUAGCUCCUGGCUCAGCACUGAUCCUGCAAAAGACCGAAUUGAAAUCACAAGCUUACUUCCCAGUAGGUCUCUGUCUGUGAACACUUUGGAUGUUUUAGGUCCUUGUCUUGUUUGUGGAACCGAUGCAGAAGCAAUUUAUGUUACUAGACAUCUUUUUUCGUAGAAGUACUAUAAUUAUAAGAUUUCAGAUAGAACAUGCAAUUAGCCUUUUGAAAUCCAACUUCUGUGCAAAAUUUUAGUAUCAGAAAAUACGAGAUUUGCAGGGGAAACAUCAGUAAACUACCAUUAAUGUCAAUGCCCAGUUUUGACUUUUGUUAGCCUGACACUCCCAAACAGUUGUAGAAUCCGAUAGAUGACUGAUGGCAAAAGAUUGUGAACAUGUGGAAGAAAAUCAGUGGGAUUCUGGUGCUGAUGAAUAGGUUGCCUUCAGAGUAUUAUUGACAGACAGCUUGUGGAACUAAUUCUUUAUUUUUGAUGUUGUGGGAAUUAACACAUCAAUGGUGGUUAUGGGAACUACCAAUGGGUUCCUACAAUUUUUAUCAGUAGUAUGUGGCAUAUACACCUUCCUAGUGGCAGUUGCCAAUGUUAAUGAUUAUUCUUUUUAUUGCAAGUAUUUCCUAUGAUCCUUCCACACUUUAUUUCCUUAAUAAUAAUAAACUUUUUCAGAAAGAAUUGAGUAGAGCAAAAAUGACAAAGAUGUGUAGCUGUGUUCAAUUUUUUUUUUUUUUUUUUUUUGAGGCAGAGUCUUGCUCUGCUGGAGUGCGGUGGUGCAAUCUCGGCUCACUGCAACCUCCACCUCCCAGGUUCAAGCAAUUCUCCUGCCUCAGUCUCCUGAGUAGCUGGAACUACAGGUGUGCGCCACCACGCCCAGCUAAUUUUUGUAAUUUUAGUAGAGACAGAGUUUCACCAUGUUGGCCAGGAUGGUCUCGAUCUCUUGACCUCAUGAUCCACCCGCCUCGACCUCCCAAAGUGCUGUGAUUACAGGUGUGAGCCACUGCACCCGGCCUGAAAUUUUUUUAAGGUGAAAAUGUUUUGACAAGUUCCUUUUUCAGAAUAGGUUUUUGAGCAGAACUCUUUCAGCUUGUUAGACCCAACUUUGCUUUUGUUUAGCUUCACAGCAUAGCUGAAAGUUGCCAAACUGGACAUUGUGCAAUAAAGUAGAAUUCUAUAUUGAUAAGCAAACUAUUUCCAAACUAAAAAUGUGAUAGAUAAAAGUGUGAUUAAUCAAAUGAUAUGAUCAGAGUAAAGAAUUUUGCCAUUUUGAUCCUUUUACUUUGUUUUAGCCACCUAUAGUGUUACCAACCAUCUUUAUCCUUGUCUGCAGGGAUAAUAAUGAACUAAUGUAGUGUUUUAAGAUAAUUUAAUGAUACUAUCUUUCCAAACUUUGUUAGAUUUUAAAUGUAUUAUUGACCUGAGACCUUAAUGACAAAUCACUGCUAUUAGACAAUUGAAGUGUUCAUUUACUUUGUAAUUCCAAUAAUCAUAGUUAUGGAAUUAUGGUAAGGUUUUGCUUUUCUGUCCUAAUAAAUAUAUAUAUUUUUUGAGAUGGAGUUUUGCUCUUGUUGCUGAGGCUGGAGUGAAAUGGCAUGAUCUCAGCUCACUGCAACCUCCGUCUCUUAGGUUCAAGCAAUUCUCCUGCCUCAGCCUCCCGAGUAGCUGGGAUUACAGGUGCUCACCACCACACCCAGCUAAUUUUUGUAUUUUUAGUAGAGAUGGGGUUUCACUGUGUUGGCCAGGCUGGUCUUGAACUGACCUCAUGAUCCACCUGCCUCAGCCUCCCAAAAUGCUGGGAUUACAGGCUUGAGCCACUGCUCCCGGCUGAUUUUUGUAUUAGUAGAGACGACAGGGUUUCACCAUGUUGGCCAGGGCUGGUCUCGAACUCCUGACCACAGGUAAUCAGCCCGCCUCGGCCUCCCAAAGUGCUGGGAUUACAGGCGUGAGCCACUUAGUAUUUGUAACCAUAAGAGAAAGUAUAUUUUAACAGCAUUACAUUUCAUGCCAAUUGACAAGUUUUGCCAAUUUUAAUAAGAAACUAAGCUUUAUGUAAUGUAACACCGUAAUUUAUGAAUUUGUUCAUUGUCACUGCCUUUAUUCAUGAAACUGUCAAAUAGAGUGUCUUUCAAGGGUUGCAGGAUCUUAGAGAUAGAAAGUACCUUGGUGAUCAUCUCCAGCCUAAAUUUCAUCAUCCCUUCUAUGGUAUUCCCAACAAAUUAUCAUCCAACCUAUACUUAAAAACAUAUGGUGGCCAGGCAUGGUGGCUCACGCCUGUAAUGCUAGCACUUUGGGAGGCCGAGGUGGGUGAAGCACCUGAGGUCAAGAGUUCGAGAUCAGCCUGGCCAACAUGGCGAAACCCCGUCUCCACUAAAAAUGCAAAAAAAAAAUUAACCGGGCGUGGUGGCAGGCAUCUAUAAUCCCAGCUACUUGGGAGGCUGAGGCAGGAGAAUUGCUCAAACCCGGGAGGCAGAGGUUGCAGUGACCCAAGAUCGUGCCACUUCACUCCAGCCUGGGCAAAAGAGCAAAACGCCAUCUCAAAAAAUAUACAUAUAUAAGGAGAUAAAGUUUCCCAUUUUCCAAUACAGUUUCACAUUUGAACAGCCCUAAUUGAUACAACUUUAUGGCAGGGUUUUAGUGUGUGAGUGGGAUCCAAAACACUCAAUCCUGUAAAAGGGUACAGUCCUAUUGUAUGUUAACACACUGAUGAUGUGAGCCUGUGAGAUGAGCCAAUCACCAGUUGUUAUGUUCGAAUCUGCUUUGUGUUGGGACGCUUUAAUGUCAGGGUUUCACUAAAUAAAUGAAUUUUCAUAUACUGAACUGAAA